AGAGCCGAGCCGGCGGCUCCACCGAACGGCCGCGCCUGCCGCCGCCGCAGCUGCAGAACCUUCCGCAUCCCCUCCCCGUCCCGCCCCCUAGCCCCAGGCGUCCGGGCCCCCUCCCUCCUUUUCCCCUCUCCCUCCCGCCCCCUCCGCGCUCUCUUUCCCUGCAGCCAGAGCCCGGCCCGCCAGCCGGGCCGGCAGGAGGGCGGCGGCGGCACAACCAUGAGCUUUGAGGGCGGCCACGGCGGCAGUCGGUGUCGCGGGGCGGAGAGCGGGGACGCCGAGCCUCCCCCGCAACCUCCCCCGCCGCCGCCGCCGACGCCGCCGCCGGGAGAGCCGGCCCCGGUCCCCGCGGCCCCGCGCUACCUGCCGCCGCUGCCCGCGUCCCCCGAGACCCCCGAGCGCGCCGCGGGGCCAAGCGAGCCGCUAGGGGAGGUGGCCCCGCGGUGCAGGGGAGCGGACGAGCUGCCGCCUCCGCCCCUGCCCCUGCAGCCCGCCGGCCAGGAAGUGGCGGCGGCCGGCGACUCCGGGGAAGGUCCGAGGCGCCUCCCGGAGGCGGCAGCAGCGAAAGGCGGCCCCGGGGAGUCUGAGGCCGGCGCGGGCGGCGAGCGCGAGCGGCGGGGCGCCGGAGACCAGCCCGAGACGCGCUCGGUGUGCAGCAGCCGCAGCAGCAGCAGUGGCGGCGGCGACCAGCGCGCUGGGCACCAGCACCAGCACCACCAGCCCAUCUGCAAGAUCUGCUUCCAGGGCGCGGAGCAGGGUGAGUUGUUGAACCCCUGCCGAUGUGAUGGGUCAGUUCGGUAUACACAUCAGCUGUGCCUGCUAAAAUGGAUCAGUGAGAGAGGUUCCUGGACCUGUGAACUUUGCUGUUAUAGAUACCAUGUUAUAGCCAUUAAAAUGAAACAACCUUGCCAGUGGCAGAGCAUUUCUAUAACACUGGUUGAGAAAGUUCAGAUGAUUGCUGUAAUCCUAGGAUCCCUGUUCUUAAUAGCCAGUGUGACUUGGCUCCUCUGGUCAGCCUUCAGCCCCUAUGCAGUGUGGCAGAGGAAGGACAUCCUUUUUCAGAUCUGCUAUGGAAUGUAUGGUUUUAUGGAUCUAGUGUGCAUAGGUCUCAUUGUUCAUGAAGGAGCUGCAGUUUACAGAGUGUUUAAGCGCUGGCGAGCUGUGAAUUUGCACUGGGAUGUGUUAAAUUAUGACAAAGCCACAGACAUCGAAGAAAGCAGCCGGGGAGAGUCUUCCACAAGUAGGACUUUGUGGUUGCCAUUGACAGCUCUGCGGAACAGAAACUUGGUCCACCCAACUCAGUUAACCUCACCAAGGUUUCAGUGUGGCUAUGUGUUAUUGCACCUGUUCAAUCGGAUGAGGCCCCAUGAAGACUUAUCAGAAGAUAACAGCUCGGGGGAGGUUGUGAUGAGAGUGACUUCAGUGUGACAAAAGCAUAAGAUGAUGCAGUGUGGACCACCCUGCACAUUUUGCAAUGUAAUUGCAGUGAAUGGCAAAACCAUAGCACUUCUAAAAACACAUCUAUGAACUUUUUAAAAUUUAUGCUUUUUAUAUGAACAUUUGAAUUGCAAAUACAUUUUUCUGAGAAAAAGAGUCCUCUUGUUCUUCGUUGUCUGGUUUGUCACAUCUUUUAUAAGUUGGUACUUGAAAUCAUUAUACAUAUAAUUUAACUAUACUUGGUUAAAAGAAUAAUGAAAGUUAUCCUUAAGGCCAAAACUAUUUUUUCUUGCUUGUUUUAAAUAUAUUUUUAUGAAAGCUUU